AGAAGAGAUUUCCUGACACCACAGCUGGAAACCCAUGUGCAUUUCAGUUCAGGAAAGAAUGCGCCGUUUUCCCUAUAUCCGGAAUUCGUCCCUGCGCAUUCCAAUACCUGAAGCGGCCACAGGGUACAGGACAGGGAGCCCUCCGACAGAAAAGAGUCGCGGCGCUAAACAAAGCCUGAUAUCACUCCGCUUCCAUAAGCCGGAUCCCCAUAAACUACGCUCUAGCUCCUCCCACUGCCGUUGUGGGUAACGCGGACGUGGAAGAACCUCGUCUGCGGAGGAAAAGUCCCAGGUGCCGAGUCAAUCCCCAUACACAGCCGCCGCCAUUGCCUCGAGUCCUUGUGUCUGACUGUCUGUUCCUGCUGCUGUAUGACACAGCACCUCGAGGCAAGGAAAUAAGAAAACUGCCUCUGAUCCAAGCAGAGAAGGUAGAUCUGUCCCCAGGUCUGUGGAACUGUCAGUUGUGAAGUUUUGUAAAAUGGUCACCCAACUUAAAACUAGGAAAUUACGAAGAAGAGAAAAUUGCCCUGUAUCUGUUAAGGUCUGCCUGUAGAUCUGCUGUAGGGCUUGUCACCAUUGGAAGCAAGGUCCUACUUCAGUGGCAGAUCUGGUGGCCUUGGAGUGGCUGAAGACCACCACCCUCCACAGGGCUGGGCCCAUGCACAGCCAUCCUUCCCUACCUUGAGUGAGCUUCCUCUGCAUGUUUUCUAUAUCACUGGCAGAGCCUGUAGUUGGAAAGGGGACAGAGUGACUACUGGACUUUGUGUGAAAACACCAACCGGGACAAAACUUCAGUCAAGGCUGAGACGGGUGGGGGUAUAUAACUUGUCCUUACGUUAAACUUGGAACAUGGUUGACUCUGGGACAGAAGCAAGGGCUAGAGGAAAGGCUGAGGCUGGCCUGCAAGAUGGAAUCAGUGGUCCUGCCACUGCUAGAGUGAAUGGUAAAACCCAGGCCGAGGCAGUGGCUGAGGCAGAACUGAAAACAGAAUCAGUGACCCAGGCCAAAGCUGGUGAUGGAGCAAUGACCAGGACACAUACAGUGACCUACAGGGAGGCUAUGGCUGUGACAAGGGAAGUGAUCAAGGUGGAAGAUACAACUAAGACUAGAGUCAUGGUUGAGACUAAGACAAAACCCCUGGCAGAACGCAGUAUAGUGCCACAAACCAAGUCAAAGGCCAUGCCUAUGUCUAGGGUCAGUACUGUAACCAAGUCUGAAGUCAAGGUUGUUGCUGUCAUUGAGGCAAAUAUUAGGUCCUAUGCCAAGUCACAUGAUAAGGCCAAUACUGGGUCCAGACCUGACAGAAGGGAAGAGACCAGCAUUGGGAUGAAAUCCAGUGAUGAGGAUGAAGAAAAUAUAUGCUCCUGGUUCUGGACUGGAGAAGAGCCUAGUGUAGGGUCCUGGUUCUGGCCUGAAGAAGAGACCUCUCUUCAAGUUUAUAAGCCCCUACCUAAGAUCCAGGAAAAGCCCAAGCCCACACACAAACCCACACUUACUAUAAAACAAAAGGUAAUAGCAUGGUCAAGGGCCAGGUAUAUUGUCCUAGUUCCAGUUGAAGGAGGGGAGCAAUCCUUGCCUCCAGAAGGAAACUGGACCCUGGUUGAGACCUUGAUUGAAACUCCUCUGGGGAUUCGACCUUUGACCAAGAUCCCACCUUAUCAUGGGCCUUAUUACCAGACCUUAGCUGAGAUCAAAAAACAGAUUAGGCAAAGGGAAAAGUAUGGGCCUAAUCCGAAGGCCUGCCACUGCAAAUCACGUGGCUUUAGUUUAGAGCCUAAAGAGUUUGAUAAACUUGUUGCCCUCCUUAAGUUAACUAAGGAUCCUUUCAUUCAUGAAAUAGCUACAAUGAUAAUGGGCAUCAGUCCUGCUUAUCCAUUUACUCAAGAUAUAAUUCAUGAUGUAGGUAUUACUGUUAUGAUUGAAAACUUGGUCAAUAAUCCCAAUGUUAAAGAACACCCUGGAGCUUUAAGUAUGGUGGAUGACAGCUCUGAGUCUUCCGAAGAACCAAAAUCAGGGGAGUCAUAUAUACAUCAAGUUUGUAAAGGCAUAAUCUCUUGCCCCUUGAACUCCCCUGUGCAGCUGGCUGGACUGAAAUUACUAGGGCACUUGAGUAUAAAAUUUGAAGAUCACUAUGUGAUUACCAGUUAUAUUCCAGAUUUCCUCACCUUGUUAAACAAGGGAAGUGUCAAAACCAAGUUUUAUGUUUUAAAAGUGUUUUCGUGUUUGUCUAAAAAUCACGCCAAUACAAGAGAAUUGAUCAGUGCCAAAGUACUGUCAUCAUUGGUUGCACCCUUUAACAAGAAUGAGUCAAAGGCCAAUAUUCUUAAUAUUAUUGAAAUAUUUGAGAAUAUAAAUUUUCAGUUCAAAACAAAGGCAAAGCUAUUUACCAAGGAAAAGUUCACUAAAUCUGAGCUUAUUUCAAUAUUCCAGGAAGCAAAACAGUUUGGUCAGAAACUCCAAGACUUAGCAGAGCACAGUGAUCCCGAAGUGAGAGAUAAAGUCAUACGAUUAAUACUAAAACUCUGAAUACCCCUCUGUUCUCAUAAAGCCUCAAACAGUUUUUUGGAGUUGCAAUAUGAAACCAAUGCAUAUUGUAAUUAUAAAUUCAAUACUUAUGUUUUCCAUGUUGAUUGAGGGAGGCAAUUUUAUGGAUACCAAUUAAUCUUGAGAUCCUGAACAUGUGCUGAUUUUUAUUGUGCUAUAUAGUAUAUAAAUUGAGAUAUUUUUGGUAUUUCUGCAACGUGACCUGAUAAUGAAUCUAUUCAUCCUGAGUAAGCUAUACUUCUGUGCUUUAUAUUGAUAUGUGUAUUCUUUUGAGAUUUUAUUUACAUGUUGUUAAUAAAGUUGCAUGCUAAAACUGGUGAAAA